GAGUCGGUGGCAGUGGUUCCGCGGUCUCCCGGUUGCUUUCAGGCCGGGGCGGAGGUUUUGCUUCCGUGGCUUCCUAGCCCAAGGGGUGAGGCUGUUAGCUGCAGUGAGCCCGUUUUCUCUUCACUCGGCCUGUCAAAGCGGCGCAGGGGCCGCGAUUAGCUUCCUGCCCCGCGACAGCUGCACUUCUGGCUUGCCGGGGCGAACCGAGGGGCUCGGAGACCUUCAGCCACGCGAGGCCCGCCAGUGAGCAGUCAGAAAUCACCUCGGCUUUGGCCCACGCCUGCUCCCCGGUGACAGUCGUCCGCCCUAUCCGCGUCUAGCUGGCGACAACCGCAGGGGUUCACUUUUGGCCGUCAGCUGUCCCUUUCCCCCCAACACAUCGCUUGACAUCUGAAGAAGUAUUUGAUUUGGAUGGGAUACCCAGGGUUGAUGUUCUGAAGAACCACUUGGUGAAAGAAGGUCGAGUAGAUGAAGAAAUUGCGCUUAGAAUUAUCAAUGAGGGUGCUGCCAUCCUUCGGAGAGAGAAAACCAUGAUAGAAGUAGAAGCUCCAAUCACAGUGUGUGGUGACAUCCAUGGCCAAUUUUUUGAUCUGAUGAAACUUUUUGAAGUAGGAGGAUCACCUGCUAAUACACGAUACCUUUUUCUUGGCGAUUAUGUGGACAGAGGUUAUUUUAGUAUAGAGUGUGUCUUAUAUUUAUGGGUUCUGAAGAUUCUAUACCCAAGCACAUUAUUUCUUCUGAGAGGCAACCAUGAAUGCAGACACCUUACUGAAUAUUUUACCUUUAAGCAGGAAUGUAAAAUUAAGUAUUCGGAAAGAGUCUAUGAAGCUUGUAUGGAAGCUUUUGAUAGUUUGCCUCUUGCUGCACUUUUAAACCAACAGUUUCUUUGUGUUCAUGGUGGACUUUCACCAGAAAUACACACACUGGAUGAUAUUAGGAGAUUAGAUAGAUUCAAAGAGCCACCUGCAUUUGGACCAAUGUGUGACUUGUUAUGGUCCGAUCCUUCUGAAGAUUUUGGAAAUGAAAAAUCACAGGAACAUUUUAGUCACAAUACAGUUCGAGGAUGUUCUUAUUUUUAUAACUAUCCAGCAGUGUGUGAAUUUUUGCAAAACAAUAAUUUGUUAUCGAUUAUUAGAGCUCAUGAAGCUCAAGAUGCAGGCUAUAGAAUGUACAGAAAAAGUCAAACUACAGGGUUCCCUUCAUUAAUAACAAUUUUUUCGGCACCUAAUUACUUAGAUGUCUACAAUAAUAAAGCUGCUGUAUUAAAGUAUGAAAAUAAUGUGAUGAAUAUUCGACAGUUUAACUGUUCUCCACAUCCUUACUGGUUGCCUAAUUUUAUGGAUGUCUUCACGUGGUCUUUACCGUUUGUUGGAGAAAAAGUGACAGAAAUGUUGGUAAAUGUUCUGAGUAUUUGCUCUGAUGAUGAACUAAUGACUGAAGGUGAAGACCAGUUUGAUGAACGGCUCAUAUAUGGCAAUAAAAAAGUAGGUUCAGCUGCAGCCCGGAAAGAAAUCAUAAGAAACAAAAUUCGAGCAAUUGGCAAGAUGGCAAGAGUCUUCUCUGUUCUCAGGGAGGAGAGUGAAAGUGUGCUGACACUCAAGGGCCUGACUCCCACAGGGAUGUUGCCUAGUGGAGUGUUAGCUGGAGGACGGCAGACCCUGCAAAGUGCCACAGUUGAGGCUAUUGAGGCUGAAAAAGCAAUACGAGGAUUCUCUCCACCACAUAGAAUCUGCAGUUUUGAAGAGGCAAAGGGUUUGGAUAGGAUCAAUGAGAGAAUGCCACCUCGGAAAGAUGCUGUACAGCAAGAUGGUUUCAAUUCUCUGAACACCGCACAUGCCACUGAGAACCACGGGACGGGCAACCAUACUGCCCAGUGACCCACUACUUCCCAGGGACUCUCACAUCUCGGGCCCCAAAUGGACAGAUCACCCGAGGAGCUGGAGGGGUCGGCCAAGCUGACUGUAAAUUUCACAGUCUCUCUGAAGAAACCAUUGUGCUUCUGAGACCCUAGCCCCCUUCCUGGAUGGAGGCUUGAGGGCCCUGGGACAUGUGCUAUCUGAUAAGAUUGGGUCAUCGCUGCCAAGGUGGAGAGCAGUGAGCAAGGGGCUUGGGGCAAUUUCCAGUGGAGGGCAUCCACACCUCCAUUUUAUGCUUGUGGUUCACACAUUUAAGUUUACAAAUCAGAUUUCUUUUCCCCUUCAGUAGAAUUAGAUUUUGUUUUUCAAUCAUGAUUUCAAAUGCAAUCCUAAGAGCUAAUGUGGACUUUUCUUUUUCCAUGAAAUGUCUUUAAAGGAUGAAUUAGCAUGGUCUUAAAAUACAUUUCUGAGGUUACUAGCUGUAUUUUGAAUUGUGAGCAAAAUGCCGAGAAACCCAGUUGGCAUUUAUACAAAAUGUUGACCUCAGGUCUAUAGUUCUUAAAUGUGGCUAAUUCUGUAACAUAGUCUUGGUAUUUUUUAAUUAUGAAUGCAUAUCCUAUUUCCAGGCAGGCUCUCUUACUUGAACACAAAUCCAAAAACUAAUUUAGAGUCUUUUUUGCCCAGAUCUUUUAAGACUUACACCCCAGAGAUUUAAGAAGAAAACCUCUAAAUUUCAAAAUUAUGAAGAAUUACAGAAUUACUCAUUUAAGGUACUUUAAAAGAAGUUUGUACAUUGUCAAAGUAAAUUUUAAUUCAAAUCAUGUCUGUAAAACUUGACGUAUUUUGUGUAUGCAUGUUUUCAUUUUGCAAAUAUUUAAUAUAUAGACCUAUGAUGUACAGGUACGACAUGUAUAGGUUACCUAGAUGUUAUGAGAAAUUUUAGUUUAUUGUGAGUACUCAAGUUGCUUAGAGAGCCACCAGGGUGAUUUGCUGCUGGCUUUCUAUCAUUUUUAUGUUUUAAUGCAAAGGAAAUUUUAAAAUGUUCUGGAAGUGUUUUUGAUUAAGCAAUGCAGCCUAGAAGCAAUGGUUCUGUUCAAUCAUUCAGAUGUUAGUGGAAGCAUAAAAGUCAAGACUGCAUGUUGAAACCUUUCUUUUGAUAGUUACUGAACUGCUUGGUUAAACUAAAUGGAACCAUGUGCUAAUUUUUCACAAUUAUUGACCUGUAUUGAUUGCCACUGUAGUUUGGUAUUUCCCUUUACUUUGGUGGCCUGCUUCCCUCAUGCCCUGGAAUACAACUCAGAGCUCCAGGCAGCGGAACCAUCUAUUGUUUUGUUUGCCAGAAAGUGCACCCUGUAUGGUCUCCUGUCUAAGUUGGAAAUAUUAUGCAUGUGCAGGACUAUUCGAGUAUUUUAUAAACAGUAGCACACAAUAAAUUCCAUGCAUGGGCCGCUGCUCCUAUCUCUGUGUUGGGUUUUAUUUGGAAGAUGCAAUCUGAUUUGUCCUUUUGAUGCAAAUCAGAAAAUCCUGUUACUAGAGCUGGGAUGUCCUCCGGAGAUUAUCUCGUGGAUAGUUCAUGGUAAUUUGAUUAAUUAAAUUCUUUAUAAAUUUUGCCUUAAAAAAAACUUUUGUUAUAUACUUGUUUUACAUGAGCAUUAGUAACUGAGCACUAGAGGACUUUGAAUGCCUACUGUAGGCCUCCUAAGUCUAAUAUUUAAGAUCACUGUUUAUUGUCUUUUAAUUGAAAGAAAAUAUGUUAUUGUCUAGAAUUUUGUUAUAGUGGUAUUGGGAAUUUACUGGGUGUUCUAACAAUAAGAAAAAUAUUAGUGAUAA